AUUCCAGUUAUGUUGCUCUCCUCCCCGCAGCCCCAGGCGGCAGCUUCGCGGCCCGGCGUCCGGUCCCCCGGUGGUCCCGGAGCGAAGCUCCGCAAUGGAGAGCGGAGGACCCUCCCUCCCCGACCUCGCACGACCAAGACCGCCCACCUUUCCCCCAACGCCCGGCUGUGGGAGCCGUUCGAGUCUUCUCCGCCAGGGCGCUCCUUCCCGGGAGGCCGCUUCUUUGGGGGAAUAAGGUCAAGGAUUACGGGAUUUGGGGAAGCAAGCUCGGCUGGGCCAGGAUUGCUUGCGUAGCUCGCUGGAAUCUAAGGCACUAGAGGGCUUGACGGCCACGUGAGGACGAACCACGCAGGCGCAGCCCCGCGCCCCGGGCAAGGACUUCCGGCAAGCCCCAAAGGGGAGCGUGCACCGCGAUGACGUCCUCAAGGCGCGCCACGUCCGCCCGGCGGCGCAGCUGCCCAGCGCAACCUCGGCCCCGCCUCGAUAGCCCCGGACCCCUGCCCCGCCCGACCCCGCCCCGCCACGGGAGCGCGCCACUCGCCCGCGCAGCAACGGCCUCAAUAGCGCCAGGCCCGCGUCUACAAGAAGCCCGACCAAGGCCGGCGUGGGCGAGGCCUGGCUAGACGCUGACGCACCGCUGGAGCUACUGACCUCGGGACGACUGGCGGACGGUCGCGGGCCUGGAGACCCAGAGCGAGACGGCCUACUUCGUUCUCGAGCCAGCAGAACGGGUUGAACGUGUCGACAACCCCACCCGCCAGUCAGCGGCGCGGGCGUGUUCGAGCCGGCUCGUGGGCGUGGUCAGGCCUCCCUGGAUGGAUGUUGGGAGAGUUUACGCGUGGCCUUGUGGGAUCGCUGUGGCGGACUCUCAGCUAUCAGAGGGCUCCAUCACUCCAUCGUAAGGAGGCAGCUGGUGGCGAGUCCUGAGCAGGGAUGUGAUCCGACGGGCAGGCGGCGCCCGGGACAGAAGCUGACGUCACACAGACCAGGCCAGUGAGGCACCCAGAGCCUGAGCCACUGCCCCGCUCCAACACUCCCACCCACCACCUCUGUCAACAGCCGGCCAACUCGCCUGGCACAGGGGCAGCUCUAGACGGGAUGGAGAGGAUGCAUCUUCAGUGUCCACACGUGGUCAACAGAUAAAAGCCAUGGCCAGAACGUUCUAAGUGGCUACAUGUGCAUCUGCCUGUUCACGGAUUCCUUCGACAAAUAUUUGAGCAUCCCCUCCUGCGACUGUGGACAGCAGAGGAGCACGCAGGCCACGUGCAGGCCACGUGCAGCCCACAGCUCUGGGGCGAGGCAGGCCCUCAACCGAACACGUAUAGAGACAGGGUUUCACCGUGUUAGCCAGGAUGGUCUCAAUCUCCUGACCUCGUGAUCUGCCCGCCGCGGCCUCCCAAAGUGCUGGGAUUACAGGCGUGAGCCACUGCGCCCCGCCAGACGUCUGCAUCUUUAAGGGGCAACACCAGCAGGUGACAUGUGAAUGGAUCUGGGCUGGGACAGAUCCCGUGGGCCUCGGCGGAGCACCUCCAGCGUCCGGGUGCGGGAGCUGAGCUGGCAAGGCCUGCACAACCCCUGCCCACAGAGCAAGGGCCCUGGCAGUCAGAGGGACAGACUUGGAGAGCAGCUGGUGGAAGAGUACCUGUCCCCUGCCCGGCUGCAGGCCCUGGCCCGGGUGGAUGACCUUCGGCUGGUGAGGACGCUGGAGAUGUGUGUGGACACUCGUGAGGGCAGCCUGGGGAACUUUGGGGUGCACCUGCCCAACCUGGACCAACUGAAGCUGAACGGCAGCCACCUGGGCUCCCUGAGGGACUUGGGCACGUCUCUGGGCCACCUGCAGGUGCUGUGGCUGGCUCGCUGUGGCCUCGCUGACCUGGAUGGCAUCGCCUCUUUGCCAGCACUUAAGGAACUCUACGCCUCCUACAACAACAUCUCGGACCUGAGCCCACUGUGCCUGCUGGAACAAUUGGAGGUGCUGGACCUGGAGGGCAACAGCGUGGAGGACCUGGGGCAGGUGCGCUACUUGCAGCUGUGCCCACGCCUGGCCAUGCUCACCCUGGAGGGCAACCUGGUGUGCCUACAGCCGGCCCCUGGCCCCACCAACAAGGUGCCCAGGGGCUACAACUACAGGGCAGAGGUGAGGAAGCUCAUUCCCCAGCUGCAGGUCCUGGACGAAGUGCCGGCCGCACACACAGGCCCACCGGCCCCCCCGCGGCUGAGCCAGGACUGGCUUGCGGUGAAGGAGGCCAUCAAGAAGGGCAACGGCCUUCCCCCGCUGGACUGUCCCCGUGGAGCCCCCAUCCGGAGACUUGACCCCGAGCUGUCCCUGCCUGAGACGCAGUCCCGGGCCUCCAGGCCCUGGCCCUUCUCCCUGCUGGUCCGUGGGGGCCCCCUGCCUGAAGGCCUGCUUUCUGAGGACCUGGCCCCAGAAGAUAACACCAGCAGCCUCACCCAUGGUGCUGGCCAAGUCCUCUGUGGGAACCCCACCAAGGGCCUGCGGGAGCGUAGGCACCAGUGCCAGGCCAGGGAGCCCCCCGAGCAGCUGCCCCAACACAGGCCAGGAGAUCCGGCCGCCAGCACUUCCACCCCAGAGCCUGACCCUGCAGACAGCUCUGACUUCCUGGCCUUGGCUGGGCUCAGGGCCUGGAGGGAACAUGGCGUGCGCCCCCUCCCCUAUAGGCACCCGGAGUCCCAACAGGAAGGGGCUGUAGCCCCCUGGGGCCCACGGAGGGUCCCUGAAGAGCAAGUGCACCAGGCAGAGCCCAAGACUCCCUCCAGCCCCCCAAGCCUGGCCUCAGAGCCCUCCGGGACCUCGAGCCAGCACCUGGUCCCUUCACCUCCCAAGCACCCAAGGCCACGAGAUUCUGGCAGCAGCUCCCCGCGGUGGUCGACAGACCUGCAGUCCAGGGGGCGUCGGCUCCGAGUCCUGGGCAGCUGGGGGCCUGGCCUGGGUGAUGGGGUGGCUGCAGUGCCUGUCCUGAGAGCCCUGGAGGUGGCCUCACGCCUGAGCCCUCGAGCCCAGGGAUGUCCUGGCCCAAAGCCAGCACCAGAUGCAGCAGCUAGACCUCCCAGGGCAGCUGAACUCUCUCACCCCAGCCCCGUCCCCACUUAAUAUAGCCCCCACUGCCAGGCUUCCCUGUGCUGGGGCCACGACUUGCCCACAUAUGUGGUCACAGAGCACAGAAUACCUGGGCGGGUGUGUUGGGGGGUGGAAGGAGUGCCUGGCCCUGGGGAGGACCCUCUUGGUGGAGGGGAGUGGGGGACUGGGACCAGCCAGGGAGGCAGCAGAGGCUGGAACCCAGUUUAGGCCCCCAACUGGGUUUGGCCUGGGGAGGGAGGGUCCGGCUCCCCAGCCCUUCCUUAGGGCCAGGCUUUCCCGCGGGCACGGGGGUGGGGGGUGGUCACCCGAGCAGGCCUGUGAGAGGCCUCUCCUGCUAGAAUUGGGCAUGGCCGAGGGGCAGGGGCUGGAGCUGCGAGUCCACCACUCCCUUGCCGGCCCCAGGGUAAGAGCCACCUCCUAGGCCGCAGUGGCCCAAGGUCCCAGCUGCUCGCCUGAGGCCGCCGGGGGUGCGGUCCAGGCCUCCCGUCUCCGGGGGAUCUGUAGGGUUCCCGCACUGCGAUAGGGCGGCCCGUUCCCUCCUCUUGGCGCAGGACGCCCCGGAACCCAAACCAACAUUUCCAGCUCUCAGGUGUACAGAAAUGCGGUUUACUUUGUAGGCCACGUUGGUUCAAUAAAUGAUGCAGCGGA